AGCACACAGGACUCGCUCCGGAACUUGCAUGGCCCACUGCGAAAGGAAAAUGCAGGGUCCCUGUUUGCAAAGCAGGACAAAAAGCGUCACUAAAGAUACUAACGUUCAAAGCUUGAAGGAUAGCGCGUUUCAAAUUGCAACCACAAAUACCAUCGUCUUCCACCAUGACUAGCCACCACCCCAUGAAGGCAGCAGUCCUUACUCAGCCUAAUUUUUUUUUUUUUUGGUAGAGACAGAGUCUUGCCAAGGCUGGAACGCAGUGCUGGGAUAUCGGCUCACUGCAACCUCCAUCUCCCAGGUUCAAGCAAUUCUCCUCCCUCAGCCUCCCAAGUAGCUGGGACUACAGGCGCCCACCACUAUGCCCAGCUAAUUUUCAGUAUUUUAGUAGAGACAACAGGGCUUUGUCAUGUUGCCCAGGGUGGUCUUGAACUCCUGAGCUCAGGCAGUCUGCCCACUUCGGCCUCCCAAAGUGCUGGGAUAACAGGCGUGAGCCACUGUGCCUGGCCCCCACUCAGCCUAAUAUUAACAACAUCAAAACAAUUGAUAUUUAUUUCUUGAUUACUCCCUAAUCCCUGGCUGAUCACUUCCCAUGCAUGGUUUAGUUUAAUCCUGAGAGGUAGUCAUUAGUAACUCCAUGCUGCAGAUGAAGAAAAUCAGGCACAGAGAGGUUAAGUAAGUUGCCCAAGUUCACACAGUUAGCAAGAUUCAACUCAAGAUUAUCUGAGACCAACACUCUUCACAAUGAUGCUAUUUUGCCUUCCCAAAAUAGCAACAGCAACUAUUUAUGGGAAAGGACACAAAUUUGGGGAGGUGAGAUGAUAGGUACCCGCUUCUCCAAGAUGCAAAACUAUCAAGGGGCAGCUCUCAUCAGCUCAUGAACCUUCCAACAUGCUGACCUCUGAAUCCAACUGUUAUCCUCACCCCCAGGGCCAUGGCUUACUCAUGAGGCCAUAGAAGAAUGGCCACAUUUGUCCAUUCCUGAUCCUGGCAGAGGCUUCUGUCUUUGGGAGAAGUGGUCAGGCUAAGGAGAGAGCUUCGUAUUCUCCAACUUGGCAGGGACCUUUGGGAUGGUCUGCUAGUCCCCAUUCUCUCAUUACAUCUCAAAUUCCAUCACUGACUGGGUUCUGGGCCCUAAGGCUGUUUAUCUAAUUUGGGUGUCAGCCAAUGACCACCCAGGAGCCAAAUCUGGUCCACUGCAGGUUUUUGUACCACCCAUGAACUAAAAAUGGUUUUUACAUUUUUAAGUAGUUGAAAAAAAUAAAAAGAAGAGUAAUAUUUUAUGACAGAAGCACAUUAUAUGAAUUCUUGACUGCCUCUGCUAAUAGAAUGUGGCAGAAGUGCCAGAAUGAUGUCUGAGGCUGCACAGCUUCUGCAGGUUUCUUUUGGGACACAUGUCUUUGAAUCCCUGAGCUGUGAUGUCACAAACCCAGCCAUCCUUAAACCACCAUGCUGCACAGAUCAUGAAGAGGAAUCACCCAGAGAUGAAAAGAAAUGCCUAAGGAGCUCUGGCUGUUUGAGCUCAGAGCCAGCAGCAUCAUCAACACCUGCCUCAGCAUCUGUAUCAGCACCAAUACCUGCUUCAGCACCUGCAUCAGCAUCAACACCCGCUUCAACAUCUGCAUCAACAUCUGCACCAGCAUCACUACCAGCAUCAGCAUCACUACCAGCAUCAGCAUCUGCACUUGCAUCAACACAUUUUUCAGCACCUGCAUCAACACCUGCUUCAACAUCUGCAUCAACAUCUGCACAAGCAUCACUACCAUCAGCAUCACUACCAGCAUCAGCAUCUGCACCUGCAUCAACACCUUUUUCAGCACCUGCUUCAACAUCUGCAUCAACAUCUGCACCAACACCAAUACCUGCAUCAGCAUCAGCGCCUGCAUCAGCAUUACUACCAGCAUCAGCAUCUGCACCUGCACCAACACCUUUUUCAGCACCUGCAUCAACACCUGCUUCAGCAUCGGUACCUGCAUCAGCAUCAACACCUGCUUUAACAUCAGCAGCUGCGUCAGAUUAGUAUCUGCAUCAACACCUGCUUCAGCAUUUGCACCAGCAUCUGCAUCAUAUCUGCCUCAGCAUCAGCACCAGCACCUGCAUCAGCAUCUGCAUCAUUAUCUGCAUCAGCACCUGCCUCAGCAUCAGCACCUGCAUCAGCACGUGCAUCACCAUCUGCAUCAUGAUCUGCAUCACCAUCGUCAUUGGUAUUGGCAUCGGCAUCAUCUGUGAGUGAGUGAGCCUUCGGGGAUUUUGGUUGCUAGCUUUUCUGCAAGCCACCCUAGCUGACACCACAUAAAGUCAGACAUAAGCUGUUCCUGCCAAGCCUUGCCCAGACUGCAUAUUUGUGAGAUGAAUAAACAAUGGCUGUUUUUGAGCCCCUAAAGGUUAAAUGAUGCGUUCAAGGUUGCUAGCUCAUAAGUGUCAGAGCUCUUCCUUGAACUCCAGCUCUGUCUGAUUCCAAAACUCCAGCUCUGAUUCCAAAGCCUCUGGCAUUGCAGGACAAGGCUUAAUGAGAUGAUGAGUGCCGAGUGCUCAAUGAAUGGGGCUGUAGUCAUUGCUGUGGUCAUUAUUAAUAUUGUAAUAAGUCAUCCCAGGCCCCCCAACAAUUUAGCGGUGAGUGGGUCUUCCAUCUGGGCCCCCUGAUUCUCAGCCCCGUGCUCUUCCCUCUCACUCCGUUAUCGAAGAAAAGCGAGAGAUGAUUGCGGGCACUUCAGGCAGGGGCUGGCACAUGGACAGCUCCAUCAACGUGAGCUGCCAUUAUGGCUUGGCAUGAGUUAACAUAGAGACAGGGGCCUACCUGCCUCCUGGCCCUCUGACUUCUGCUUCUACCUGGCCUUGUCUCCACAUGCCAACAAGAUUUAUUCUCAUCGAUGGAUCCAGUGACUACUGGUUGCCACAAACCUAGGACCAGCCAAGACCCAGUUAGCAGCCCAGGGUCUUCCCCAAGAAGUAGACCUCACCCCAGCAAGGUCAGCUCACAGGAUGAGAUGCGUUUUUGCAUUUGGUGGAGGCAGCCGACAUCUACCAAGUACAUGUUUCACUCCUAGGAGAGAACACUCUGGGACUCAGAGGCUGGAAGCUCUGCCAGCAGGAACCAGGCCCUGGAGCCUCUGUGACUCAUCCUUUCCCCAAGGUCAAUCGUUGUUUUGAAGGUCAACUGUCCUCAGAGCUCUGGAAGCCAUGCCUUUAGUAGGUCAAGUUUGCAAGUACACCUCCUGGUUCCCUUUCCUUGUCUGCACCCCUCCACGGCCUUUAUCUGAACUUCCCCCUAGUGUGUCCUGUGCUUUUAUAAAUAGUCCUGAGAUGUUUCGUUUUAAA